GAGGCCCUGUCUAGGUAGCUGGCACCAGGAGCCGUGGGCAAGGGAAGAGGCCACACCCUGCCCUGCUCUGCUGCAGCCAGAAUGGGUGUGAAGGCGUCUCAAACAGGCUUUGUGGUCCUGGUGCUGCUCCAGUGCUGCUCUGCAUACAAACUGGUCUGCUACUACACCAGCUGGUCCCAGUACCGGGAAGGCGAUGGGAGCUGCUUCCCAGAUGCCCUUGACCGCUUCCUCUGUACCCACAUCAUCUACAGCUUUGCCAAUAUAAGCAACGAUCACAUCGACACCUGGGAGUGGAAUGAUGUGACGCUCUACGGCAUGCUCAACACACUCAAGAACAGGAACCCCAACCUGAAGACUCUCUUGUCUGUCGGAGGAUGGAACUUUGGGUCUCAAAGGGCUGAUUUUGGUCCUAGAUUUUCCAAGAUAGCCUCCAACACCCAGAGUCGCCGGACUUUCAUCAAGUCAGUACCGCCAUUUCUGCGCACCCAUGGCUUUGAUGGGCUGGACCUUGCCUGGCUCUACCCUGGACGGAGAGACAAACAGCAUUUUACCACCCUAAUCAAGGAAAUGAAGGCCGAAUUUAUAAAGGAAGCCCAGCCAGGGAAAAAGCAGCUCCUGCUCAGCGCAGCACUGUCUGCGGGGAAGGUCACCAUUGACAGCAGCUAUGACAUUGCCAAGAUAUCCCAGCCUCCCCCUUUCCUGUUGGCCCCACGCCUCAUCCUCACCCCACCCCUCAUGCCUGUGAGGAACAAGGAACAGCCAAGCAGCCUCAUCUCUCCUGAGAGCAGAGCCAUGGGUCUCGGGAAACCCAGGAGUAAGGAACAAAGACUCUUCAAAAUGACUUCAGAGCUUUCUUUAGGAUCCCAGGGAGGUGUAAACUCAGUGCUUAAUUAAAUGGAUUCUUUAGAGGGUGGGAAACAGGUGGAUGUCAACCAUUUGCCCCACAUACCCGUAUUCAUGCAAUCCACCCCCAGUGGGCUCACCGGUGCGGGUGUGCAAAACCUCCUCCCACCCCAGUCAUCUUAGGUUCAGGUCAUCCUUUGGUCCUGCUCUUUCCCCGCCAGGCUGUCUGUUGAUGCUACUUUUAAUCUGCUUUCACUAAGAUAAGCCUGGCAGAAGUGGUGGGGGUAAGGUGGGCUGUAGGCCAGCUCCCAAAUGUGUGCUGGGCAUAACAGAAGACCCAUUCUUGACUGAAGUGCCCUUGUGGGACCCUGAGCCCGUGCCCUGGAGUGGCACAGGGAGGUGUGCCAGCAAUGGGGACCGAGGUCACUGGGGACUGCUGGGGUUCGGGCUAGUGGCCUGUCUGGCUGCUGUCUGCUUCCCUCGUUCACAUCCUGCUGGAGCCUUAAAUAGGAGCCCAAAAGCUUUUCUUUCUUACUUUUUUUUGAGACAAAAUCUCACUCUGUUGCCCAGGCCGGAGUGCAGUGGCACAACCUCUGCCGCCUGGGUUCAAGCGAUUCUCCUGCCUCAGCCUCCCGAGUAGCUGGGAUUACAGGUGCCUGCCACCAUGCCUGGCUAAUUUUCGUAGUUAGAGUAGAGACGGGGUUUCACCAUCUUGGCCAGGCUGGUCUUGAACUCCUCACCUCAUGAUCCACCUGCCUCGGCCUCCCAAAGUGCUGGGAUUCCAGGUAUGAGCCACCACGCCCGGCCUAAAGCUUUUCUAUUAAUAAUUUCCUGCCUCACCCUCCAUCCCCUUCCUCCUCAGACACCUGGAUUUCAUUAGCAUCAUGACCUACGAUUUUCAUGGAGCCUGGCGUGGGACCACAGGCCAUCACAGUCCCCUGUUCCGAGGUCAGGAGGAUGCAAGUCCUGACAGAUUCAGCAACACU